CGUUGGCCAGGCUGAUGUCGAACUCCUGGCCUCGGGUGAUCCACCUGCCUCAGCCUCCCAAUGUGCCUAUGGUCUUUAACAUACCCUCAGCACUUCAGCACACUUCCAGCAGAAACUGUAAUAUACAGAUGACUCUGCAUUUGAUGGUAGUUUUUUUUAACAAUGUGUUAAUUCAUAAUGAAAACCUAUUAGGUUAUAUAAGCCCACCCUGUACACAUAGUCACCUGGCAUGUGUCUCUACAUGCCAAUAACAAGUAACCAAGAAAGGCUAGAAAGACCUAACACUUGACCAUUUUACAUGUGAUGUUUCAAAAGCCAACUGGAAAAUUGAUUAUGGGUUUUCUGAUUCCAUUGUUCCUUUUAUUAUACUAUGCUUCCUUGGAAUUAAAAAAAAGGAAUGUCCCACCUUGUCACAUUUUAGUUCCCUUGGAUUUUUUAACAUUUAGUAGCAUUUAUGUUAAAAUGUGUUUCACUUUAAAAUUUUUUGCAUGAGUGAGGAAAGCUAUAUAUUUCUUCACUUUCAUUCAUUCAUUAUUCAUGAAAUCAGAACACAAAUAGACUGUCAGAAUACAGCCAAAGGGCUGAGUGUAGAGUAAGAAGGUUGCUGUUACCAUAUAAAGUGCUAUAAAAAGUCGAAACAAUAAUGGCGGAUAGAUAUAUAAUUCUUCUUGAGAAAAAUGUGCCAAGUUUCACAAAGCAUUAGUCAUUAUAUUCAUUUCUAUUUUCAAAGCCCCAGGCAUUAGUUUGGAUUUAUUUGUUCUUUGUUGAAUGGUCAAAUUAUACUGUGACUGCAUGUAUUGCACUGUAUAAUACAAAUCAUUACUGAAUUCCCAUGAAAUGCUUCUGUAAAAUACUUCUGGUAUUGCUGAACAUUUUUUGUCUUACUCAGAAAAGUAUAAAUUUAUAGGCAUUUUCUUAAGAUAGCUACUUCAGGCUAUAAAAAGUAGAUGCCCCAAGUAACUUGCCAAGUUUAGAAAUGCAAGUAACUGAAAAGUAGCUUGGCAAACUAAAGGAGUUCACUCAAAUUAUUAAAUAAUUUGCAUUCAAGGUGUUAUAUUUCUUGUUGAAUUAGGAGAUACUUAUUUGCCAGGAUAUUAUUCCUAUUCAUAGCUAAAGAUAAGGUAUUUUUAGCUAUGUCUUCUUAAAAAAAAAAGCGGUUCUCAUUUUUGCAUUUCAGCAUAUUUUACAGUAUUCCUCCCGGAUCAAACAUCAAGGAAAUAUAUACAAAAUGUAGACAAUAUGAGAAGACAUAUUUGCUAAUUGUCUCUUCAUAUGGGAAAGUUCUCACAACUCCAUUAGGGAUUUGGAGAUGAUGUAAUUGAUAAUAUAUAAGCCCAGUGUCUUUUGAGGCUGCUGGAUUCCUUAGAGUAUUGCCAGCCAACAAAAUCCAGACAGUAAUUUGAAAGUGGAAUUUGAAAUACCAUCAGAUAACGUGUGACCAGCUGGCCCAGGAGACCUUCAGUGAAUAGCAUGGUAAUUCAUGGCACCUAACAUGAAACUCCAACUUUACCCAUCUGUCACUGUUCAACCUCAGUUUGGUCAGCUGAGUCAUGUACAGUACAUUAUCCUGCAAACAGACUAAUCGAUCUAACCUCCCCUCUUUCAGGGCUCUUUCAUCAUUACUGGGUGAAAAACUCACCCUGCCAAAGGAAUGAUCAGUAUGAACACGUUACUGUAGCUAGAACAUGUCACAGACUGUUCAGAUGUUCUCCACAAUAUUAGACGUUUGAUACCGUGAAUACAUGCACAGGAAAAAGAAAUUGUUCACGUAUAAAACCAUCUGACUUGAAAACUACUGCUAACAAAUGGACAUGUGUACAUCCAUUAGACAAAGUGUCCGAAAAUCCAAGCGCUAUCCUCUAGAUUUCACAAACCUGUUUCCUGAAAAUACAUUUGUUUAUGUAAGCCUGCUUACUUUCAUCUCCAAUUCUUUUUAUCAUAAGUCACAUUGACUCUAUCUGAAAAUCUUUAUGUUGGUUAUGUGACUAAAUUUUGAUUCAUUGUAUGCCUUAAGCGUUCAAAUAUUCAUAUAUUUUCUUGACUACAUGACUAUUGAAUAAAUGCCAUUGUCAAAAACCUUAAAUAUUUCUCCUUAAAAUUUAAGAAAUAUUUACCACUAUUUGGUAAUUUAAUAAAAUGCAUUUGUAUUUCCCUUGAUGACCAUGCAAAAACAGUAUAAAAACUUGGUACAUACUUUAUCACUAACAAACCAGAUUUUCUUCAUUUGUCUUAGGAGACAUAUUGGCUCAGCAAAUAGACGGUAGAGCCUUUGACAGUGGGAAAUUGAGUGUAACAUAUAGUGUAAUCAACACUUAGGUUUUCUUGCUGUGUGGAUCUGAAGAACAGUUUCAUGCAUUUUCUAGUUUUUAAUAUAUGUAGCUCUCCCAUUUUGUUCUGAGUUUUCCAUUUGAAACUUAUUAUUUACAAUUUUCCAAAAGGCUUGAGGUCCAGUAUUUUUUUCCCUCUAAAAUAUUAGAACAGACUUCUAAAUUCUAGGAUUAAGGGAUUCUGUUAUCUUGAAGAUAACAUCGGUGUAUCAGAAUACUGUAUAUAGGAAGGAACCUGGGUCCACCUCCCCACACGGGUACAAAUUUUAAAUAUUUAAGUCACCUGGUGGCCUUUGACAACCAAGAUGAUUGUAGCAGAAGGUACUGUCCUCUUGACUGGUAGCAAGAUGAUUAAAAGUAAAGUCUCCCGAGGUAUAUUUCUAUAUUUAGAAGUACACAAUUUCAGUAGCCACUUUUCAAUAUUUUGUUCAAAAACAUAUAUUGAUUUAUAUCUGCAUACAUCCUACAAAUGCCCAUGCAAUAAAUAUAAAAAGAAGCAUCAUUUGGAGCAAGACAAAAUAAGCAUUAGAAUCCAGCCAAUUCAGGAAGCAACAGUAAUCUAAUAUUUUCUUUCUGAUGGCACUUUGUGUUGCCAUCACUUGUAAGACACAAGUACUCAUAGAAACCACUGUGAUCAGACACCAUCCUCUGUGGCCUCCCCUGAGUCCUCAGUUUGUAUGGGGAACAUCAUGGUUUAAGCUCACAGCUGUGAAUCAUAGAUUCUCCAUGUCUGGUCCAUGCAUGGACUUUAUGGAACCCGUGUAUUCCCUGACUUCUUUUCUCAUUUAUGUAUCUAUGGCUUUCAUUGAUUUGUCAAGAACUAUUGUUUUAAUUAAUGGUUUUCUUCCCAGAGUACAUGUAAUGUCCUUGUAAGAAUAACAAUAGCUAAUAAUUAUUAAGUAUAUUCUACUUGUCAGUAUGCCUGUAAGACUUGAAUUAAUUUAUUUUUCUUCACAAUAAUCAGAUGCAGCAAAUAGUAUUCACACCGAUUUUACAAAUGAGAAAAUCAUGGUAAGAUAGUUUAAGAAAUUGUCGAAGCUCAUACAUCUCAUUAGUGACAGAGCAAGAAUUCAAAUGUCAAAACGCCUAUGCAAAGUCUAUACUGUUAACCAGAAAGCUAAGCUUUCUGAAAAUGUAGCUGGUUUUAUCCUGCAGAACAUAUUCUGCCUAUGGGUUUCCAUGUAUCUUCUUAGUAUACAUAUCUUGCAACCAAGGUCUAGCUUAUAAGUUAUUUUUGCCGUAGUUUAAAAUUAUUUACCAUAUUUUUAUUGAAGGGGGAUUUCAAAUUUAGUAAAACUAAUCAAAAAUUUCCUAUUUUGUUUUCCUUUAAAGCCUAUUUUACACAAAGCAGAACCUAUCUAAAUACAUUUUAACUUAUGAAACAGAAGUUUACUUAUUGAAUGAGAGGAAAACGUCUAAUUACUCAGUGAUGGUCAGGGUGCCCUUUUCACUCUCAAAUUCUGGCAAAAUAUAUGCUUAGUGGAGACAAUAAGGAGUAUAUGUUGAAGAAAUGAUUGUGAGACCAUUUAACAAAUAUUUCAACUCUAAACAAAAAAGUCCUGUACUAAGUACCGAGUAAGGGAAACAGAAUUUGAAGUGACCUUUCCCUGGCUCACCAAUGGUUUUAGGAUUUAGAGGAACAAGAGAGUAUAAAUAUGGAAAAGUAAUAUUGAAAGUCUUAUAAGAAAACAUAAAUGAAAAGAGACUAUUAAUUUAGCAGUGACUUUGAUCUAAUCAUAACUAGAGGAAUAUAAGAAAGUUAUCUCCCAAAUCAAAAAAAAAAAAGUACAAAAUGGUUUCAUAUCCUCUCCUCUAAAAAAUUAGUCCAAACAUAAAAUCUCUGAAAAUGAAAUUAAUUGACUUGAGUUCAGCACCGUGUCUAGUACAAUGGUAGUAUGGUCUUGAGUAAGCCAGUUAGAUACCUAGGAUUAUCUCUCAGUGUGGAAAUAAUAAUACCUCUUCACUUACAUAUCAUGAAGGUCACAUGAAAUUUUCUCUUUGCACAGUUCUAGAACACUUUAAAACUUUAGUGUACUUUUGUACACCAUUUUAAAGUAACCCUACUCCCCAGCAAAGACAUUUAAAAACUGAUCAUGCUUUUUGCCAUGUUAAAAAAAUAAGAGUUGUCAAGAUACUUGAAUUUUAGUCCCGGUAAUUUCACAAUCUAAGUUGUGACUUCAGCAUGUCAUUUAAGUUUUCCAGUUCACAAGCCAAACAAGUGAAUUAGAUAAGAUGAUCUUUAAUACUCAUUUCUUUUCUGUGAAUUGAAUACUGUGUAAGGAGAGGAGGAAAUUUUCAUUCACCAGAAAUAAUGUAUUUGAUAGUAUUUAUUUAUUCAAUAACUAUUUAUUGGCUGCUGACUCUUUGCUUGGACUUAGAGAAAUGAACAAGAGAAAUAAAGCCCAGACCCUGAGAGAACUUUCUAGAUGGGGAGACAGACAACAGACAAGUAAACAAAUAAAUAGGUAAUUUCAGAAAAUAAUAAGCACAAUGAACAAAAACAAGACAGGGUAAGAGUUUUUUUAUUAGCAGAUUCCUUUACCAUAUUACUGGUAAAAUUAAACAUCCUUGGUAUUUUGUAAUUUUUUCCCCUUUCUUAAAAUGUCUUUCCUUCUCAGUAAACUCUUUCGACCUAUGUGCUUAAUUUCCUCCCCAAGUAAUCUCCUUCUUAAUUUUCUCCAUGUUCACUGACUUCUUCCUGCCGCAGACAGCCAGGCACACCUGUUUCUUAUGCUAUUUACUGCCACAUCUGCCAGCCCCAGGUGGGCUCCAGUUGACACAAUCCAGGUGCAAACAUGCAGUGCACACACUCUGUGGCUCUUAGUUCUGCUCCAUGGCUUUCCUGUUGACACCGGGGCUUAGAAUUCCAUGUGACCCUGAUGGGUACUUAUGCAUGGACAACUAGAAAGUGUAGGGAUGUUAACGAGCCAUAGUAUAAACCUUUCUCUAAUGCGAGGUGGAAACCAGAGAUUCGAUAUUUUUCUCUUUUUUUCUCCUCAUAUGGAUUGGCUUGAGGCACAGUUUUGUGGCAUUUUACAAGACAACUGUGCAGGACGUAGAAAUGUUUUGCUCUGAGAUGUGUAUAAGCGUAAUAAUUCAUCAUUAUAUUGGCUUUCCCUUUCUUACCUGUCCCUUAGUGCUCCUUCCGUAAUUGUCCUAUCUAAUAAAGUAGUACCACUUAUGCCUUUGCUUCAGGCUUUGCAUUUUCUAACUAUUUGUGCUUCCAUGGAACCAGGAAUGGCUUUAGACAACACACCCUCAGGACAGAUUUUAGGAGUUGGAUUACUCCCCUAUGUGACAGCAACGAGGAUCUGAUUUCUGGUUGUAAACACAUGGUGAUAACUCUAGGCAUGUGGUAGCAUCACAAUUACCAACACUUCCUCUUGUGGUUAACUGAGAUGUGGUGCAGGUGGAAGAAGAUGUGUUGGGAUCCUCAGUAGCCGCAUACCUAGACUUCCCUACCCAGACAGAGGACUCAGUGUUACACUCAGCAUCUCCAACCCUAAGAAAGAGGUGCAAUGUUGGGGGUUUCUUUGGAUUUUGGAAACAACAUAUAUCAUAAUAUUUCAGAAUAUUUUUUCAAUGCAUUUAUUGCUUUACUUAGAAGGUUGCCCGUUUUCAGUGGAGUCCAGAGCAAGAAAGGGCUCUUCAGCAUGUGCUGGCUCUGCUGCAAGCUUUCUGUCCCUGGAAGUCUGUGACACAGUAGAGAUAGUGCUGCUGAUGUCUGCGGUAUGGAAGAAUGGUGAGUAGAGGUCUCCAGCAAGCCCCAAUAGGAAUUCUGUAAUGCAGACACCUAGAGAUUUGGAAUGAGUUCAUGCCUUUUAUGGAGAACUGUCCUCCAUUGUAAAAUUGUCUGUAGCAUGAUUCUGGCACUAGUGGGGACUGAUUAUUGGACCAUGGGGUACCAAGUACUUAUGUGACAGAAGCCACCCUUUGUAAGUUGAAAAACUGACCAAAUCUUAAAAUGAGGUGGACAUAGCAGCAGUCCACUUUAUAAUGGAAUAUUCGGGAUCAAGCCCUAACUAGUACAGAUGACACAAGAUAUUAUGAGGACAAGUGGCACAGACCCCCUUGUCACACGUCCUUAAUUAAUGCCCUGGCACCUUUCUUCUGUCUAUGUAUAUGGCCUCAUAGAGGAUUCCCUGUGAACUACUGAAGAAAAAGGAAGCCAUCCAGGCACAUCCAGGCAUGGCUCACAAAUAGUUAACAAGGUAGUCUAUGCUGGCGAAAAGUUGAUUUUUGCUGCAUUUAACUCCACUCAUGAAUGUCCCAGGAGGACAAUAGCAAAGAAGAGUUGUCUUAGUGACCAGAGUUGUUUGCCUUGGGCUCUGCUUUCUGGGGCAACAUUGGUUUGCUGUCUUCAAAGAUCUGCUUAUGUUCCCUCUCACUUCUGCUAGCUGCUCUUCUUGCAGUUACUGUAUCACUCCUUGCAACUGUCAGUAUUUGCCUUAAACUUAUGAUCAGGGCUACCAGAAAUACAAUGAUUAUAAGCCACAUUUUCGGUUCCAGUACUGUAGAGUACAUUCAUUUAUGCAAAGGAAGUCUGGUUCAAUGAAGUUCAAAGUCAGCUGAAAGGCCAAAAAAAAGGAUGCAAAGGCAAAAUGCAGACUGGGAAGUGAGGGUCUAAGUAAAUGAGGUGAGUUGACUUUGGUGGAGUAGAUGGUGUGUUUAUAGGAUGAUUGUGUACAUAGAUGCCUUAAAGGAACUUUGUUUUAGUUCUGAAUGGCAGCACCAUCUCCCCACCGCCAUACCCCUCUCCUCACUCUGGGACCCUGGGUCAUUACCCAGAGCAGUCAGCAGGGAGCUCCCCAAGCUUGGCCUCCGCUCUGUGCACCCUGUGAUCUGUCUUAACCAGGUUAUUCUUGUCUUCCACUUGUCAUAAACCUACCUAAAUGACAACCCACUGAUCGUUAUUAUUUAAAGCUUAUUUAAAGCAGUGUUUUCAUUGACAAAGAGUUCACAAGAGAUGUUCAGGAAAAUAAAUUUUCACGGUCACGUGAGUUUAGGAAAUGCAAUGUAACAUGUCUCCCUUUUUUGAAAAUUUGUCAGGCACAUUUACAUAUUAAAAGGCCUUAAAAAGAGAGUAAAAGGAAAUAAAAAGAUACUUUUAUCCUUAUUUAAUUCAGUGAUUACCAAAUGUAUAAGCCUACAUAAUUCCAUUUUAUCUUUGUUUUAAAUACCAUCUCCACUCCUUCCCCCGCAAAUGUUUCAUCCCUCUCUCAUCAUUCAGGGAGAAAGAAAAGUCAUCAUAAUAACUUUGAAGUAUUCCUGUGGUACAUUAGUGUUCAAAGAAUUUUGGAGUUGAAAAGGACCUUAGAGAAUAUCUAAUCUAUUGGGUCACAAACAUUUUAUCACCAAAAACCAUUUUACUUAAAUCUCUCCACAUAUAUACAAGUUUUAAAAGACAACUUCUACCACUUAGAAAAUUAUAAUAUUCUCUCUCUUUUUUUUUAAACCAGCAAAGGGGUAGAGAGCUGCCUUCCAAAGCCUUUUAUUAACAUUGAGUUAUAUAUUUAUUCUGGCACUUUAAUAAUACUUUGAGCAAAAAAAUCAAAGGACCUUGACAUUUCGGUUGGCAAACUUUUAAGUUUUUUUUUUUAAUGACUUCUUAUUUCUAUGAUCUCAUAAGGAUAGGAGAUCUAUAUUAUGCCCGUCCUCAACUAUUUAUUGAUAACAUACCUUGGUUUCAAAAAGUUGAGCGUCGUACUCUAGGCCCACUGCUGUUUGAUAGAACUCAGAGCUCCUAAUUCCCUGAUCAAUAUUCUUCCUAUUGCCUUUGAUGUUUCUUUAGAGCAGAAGUUGGCAAACUUUUUCUGUAAGUCAGAUAGUAAACAUUUUAGCAUGUGUGUCAUAAAGUCUCUGUUGAAACCAUUCAACCUCAUUGUUGUAGUGCGGAAGCAGUGAUAGACAAUAUGUAACAAAUGGGUAUGACUGUGUUCUAAUAAAACUUUAUUUACAGAAACAGGCCACAGGCUGUGAGCCACAGUUUGCCAACCCUUCCUGUAGAGCACUUUGCCAUACACUUGCCUGAUUAUAAGAAUUAUCUGGCCUAUGAAGUAAAAUAUGGAUUCCACUAUCUCUUCUGAUUCUGAUUGAGGAUAAGGCCUAUAAAUCUGUGUCCUUUUCAAACACAUCAGGUGAUUUUUAUUUUUGGAGGAACAAGUUUGUCAAACAUUGAUUUGGGUAUACUUAUUCUUUUUUUUUUUGUAAUAUUAGAAAACCACAUGUAUUUAUUUCCAGGCUGAAGUAUUUAGUAUUUUCCAAUUUGUACCAGAUCAAGUUUGAGUCAAAGAAACUGAAUAUUUGGCUUCAGUUUGGUUUAACAGAUUAAUUUGAAUCAAAUCAUUGGCUUGUGGUGCUUGUAGUUUAGUUUAUGGUACUGCUUCUUAUAUGAACCCUUAAAUGAUUUAUUCCUGGUUCAUUUGCGGUUCUUCAAUGGGAAUAGCUUGAAGAAGGAUCCAGAAUCAUUCUCUAAAGGAUUUGAUGCCUGUUUAAGAAAAUAUGUUAAUGUACACUGUAUAUAAUAUACUUGUUUUUAUAUAUACAUACAGUAUAACCUCACAAGAGAAAUUAUGGCUAGUUAGAAGUGGGGAUUUAUAAAGGAAUUAAAAGUAAUCAAUAUUAACAUGAUGUUGUACAGUUGAAAAAGUACAUUUUUCUCAUUUGAUAUUUAUAAUCCUGGGAGGUCUUUUUGUUUUUUCUUUUUUUAUAGCUGAAGAAAUUCAGGCUGAAAUCACAAAGCUGGUAAAUGGAAUUGGGACAGAAACUGAAGACUUUAAAUCUCAAAUUAUGUGUUCUUUCUCCUGCAGUCUAGAAGAUGCAAAUAAAAGAGGCAUAAUAGCAGAAGUUAGGAAAAACAGAUGAACCAAGGAAAAGCUUUUUAUGAGUGUCCAUCGCUCCAGUGAUCCCUGAUCCAAACAGAAUCCUAGACUCUUAAGAGCUACUUCUACACUGUCUUAAAACAAAGCUUGAAAAAAUAUCUCUAAGUGUCCUCCCAUCCUCUGCUCUCUUAGAGAAAACCUUUUACAGCACUGAAGGACCUUCUGCAGCUUGAAAAAUCCAAAUCAAGAGUCCACACUUGAUAAGGCCAUGGAGGGAUUCUGUAGAGAGGAGGACUCGGCCGAUGAGGAAGGGAGGGCUCCUGAGGAUUUGGCAGAGCUGGGUCCUCACCUGCCUUCUCUAUAAAGUCUUUCCCAGUUUUCCUUUUCAUAGCUUUCUGAAAACCUGGUCAACUCUUCUUUGAGUCCUCGUGCAGCCUUUUCAUGGUUCUUUUAAUACUUUUCAUACACUGCCCUCUUGUAAGGUGUUACAGGAUCCUAAUGAAUGCCUUCUGUAUUGUUGUAUUCCAUACUAGUUAGGGCCUAACAAAAGCAUGGCAUCGAAUUGUGUAGAGGUGACUGAUAAAUACAAGAAGGAAAGAAGAAAGAGUGGGGAGGAAAUAAGGGGAAAGGAAGACAGAAAGAAAGAGAAAGGAGAGAAAAAGUCAACAGAGCAUGAGACAUAGCAUUACUAAUUGGCUGAGGAAUAUCAAAGUUAGUAUCUCUACCCUAUUAUUUUCCUAUUUCUUUCCUGUCCCAAAGCUAAGCAAGAGUGGAAUUAUCUCCCCAAAGUCCCUUGUCCUCCUCUGAUUGUUACAGCUGGAUCAGGGUCCUAUUAAUUGAUGAUGAGGGUCACUUGCCUGUUUCCCCAGGUAACCAUGAGCACCUUGAGCUAAGUCCCCUUUCUUAGAUACCAUUUUAACCAGUUCCCCUGACUCCAGCCUUUCUGCUCAUUUUAUUGCAUACACAAAUGUCAGGUUAACCUGCAGCACAGUUGUAGUAAACAGACAAAGGCUUGCGAUGUCUCCACACUGCCCAGGAUGGCCUGCAUACUUGAGCUGAUCUACUAGCCCUUUGCAAUUCACAAUGAUGUGCAAAAUAUUGCCUCAAUCUGGUAUUCCUCACUCUUUGUUAAUUCUGUCUUUCAAAAUACAUUCUGAAAAUACAUCUCAAAGAGAAUCUCACAGUCCUCAAAAUCUCUUAAAAUUUCCUGUUUCCCUGAUAUGUGGUAUUCCUCUCAUUCUUAUUUCAUGAGAGGUACAAUUGUAUAAAAAAAGUGCUUGCAAGCCUGAAAGAUGUACCCUUUGCCACAUUCAGUUCUAUGCCCUUAGGUAAUUUGCUUAGCCAUUAGGAAUCUGUGUUUCCAAAUCUUCAGAAAAGUGUCUUAGUCCCUUUUUGCAUGCUGGCAACAAGUGAAAAACUACCCUGCUUGUAGCAGAAGCUUAAACUCCUGUGAUGAAUGACAGAAGCAACAGCAUCUAACCCUGGGGGCACAGAGAGACAGGGACUGAGAAGAGUAAGGGACAGGGCAGUUGGAUCCAGAUGGGCUUCUGUUUUUGUACGAUCAUGAUCCCUUCUUUACUUGUUAGUAUGACCAGCAAGACAUUAAAAAAUAUUUCCUUUUUCCAAGACCAUAUAAGGAAAUAAAACUAUUUAGCAAUCUGAUCUCUCUUCAGAAUGCUUUUCAUUAAAUGAUAUGAGUAUUUAUUGCUUAAUAGUGGACUCUUCAAUGCCAGCAUCCCCCAGUAACAAAUUAGUAUAACAGUAUGCUCUUCCACUUGCUUCAAAACGUGCUUUCUGAUUACUGUCAUAAAAAAUAGGCCAGGCAUGGUGGCUCACGCCUGUAAUCCCAGCACUUUGGGAGGCUGAGGUGGGCGGGAUCACGAGAUCAGGAGAUCGAUCGAGACCAUCCUGGCCAACAUAGUAAAACCACGUCUCUACUAAAAUACAAAAAAUUAGCUGAGCGUGGUGACACGUGCCUGUAGUCCCAGUUACUCGGGAGGCUGAGGCAGGGUAUCGUUUGAACCUGGGAGGCGGAUGUUGCAGUGAGCCGAGAUCAUGCUACUGCACUCCAGCCUGGUGACAGAGCAAGACUCCGUCUCAAAAAAAAAGAAAAAAAAAAAGAACUCAACCUAAUGAUAAAAUAAAUAUGAAGUAGUGCUAAUGCUGUUCCACAAAAAACUUCCACUUAAUCAUUAACUAAACUGUUUACAAAAAUAUUUCAUGGGAAAAUUUAAUCAGAUUUAUUUUUUAUAUUUGAACAAUAGCAAUAACACCUUAUGCCAGUUGCUUACAAAACCUUAGCUAAUUAAUGUUAUUGGAAAAAUUGGAUAAAAAUUUAGACUCUGGAGCCACCCACAGAUUUUUAAUUCAUUAAAUCUGGAACAGGGCCCAGGAAUUUACAUUUUUAAAGAAGCAGAUGCUUAAACUGUGACAAUAAUUUAAGCUUGUUUUCAUUGCGGUUUCUUCCUGCACCUAACAUAAUCAUUAUUUGACUUAUAAGCUAGAUAUCAGCUGCCCAUACUAAUUGCAUUGCUUGAGAAUCUCUGCAAUGAGAAUGCUGCCUCAAAAUUACUAUUAUUUUAGAAUGUGGUCUCCUGACUUGAAUUUUCAACUAGCUCCUUAGUGAUAACAGUGUCUAGUGAUAUAGGAUCUACAUUUCCCAAACAUCCAACUGCUACCACAGCCAUCUUGCUGUGCACAAGCAGCAGUGUGGAAAACACACACACAAAAAAAGAUUCUGCAGAAUAAUUAUCUGAGAUGUGAAACUGCAUGUUCUUUCCCCCUCUCUCUCCAGCCACCCUCAUUUAGACUGUUUAAAGCAACGAUGCCAGUGCAUUUUUAUUUCAUUAGGGGCAUUUAUAACCACUGGAUUUGUUUUAAUUUUGAAGAAUUACAAAUACAGAAAACUCGAAGAAAUAGAAGUAGUAAAAACCCAUUUACACUCUAACUCAGCAGUUAAUAUUUAUCUUGUUUACUUAUUUCUCUUUCCUCUCCAUGUCUCUGUCUACCUAACUGUACUUUUUUACUGGGUCUUUGAAAGUGAGUCGCAGACAUGAUGAUACCUACCCUAUAUAUUUCAGCAUCUCUUCUAAUUAAAAAACCUUCACUUACAUAAAUGCAAUACCAUGAUCACAACCAACAUAUUUAAUACUGAUAAAAGAAUACAGGUACAUUUGAUGUUUUCUUCUUCCACAACUGACCUAUAGCGAUUUUUAUUUUAUUUUAUUUUAUUUUAUUUUUUGCUCCAGAUUUCAGUCAAGAACCACUUGUUUGCUAGGCAUGGUAGUGGUACAUGCCUGUAGUCCCAGCUACUUUGGAGGCUGAGGCCAGAAGUUCAGGGCCAACCUAGGCAACAUAAUAUAAUGAGACUUCAUCUCUUAAAACAAAACAAACACUUAAACACUUAUUGCAUUUGGUUAUCAUAAUCUCUUUAGUCUCCUUUGAUUUAGAUUAAUUUAUCUACCUGCCUUUUUUUCAUUUUUAUUCUUUUUUUAUUUCAAAAUAUUGACAUUCUGGAAGAGUUUAGAAACUUGUCUCUUAUAAUACCCUCCAACCUGAAUUUGUUGUAAUUUUUCCUCAAGUUAAACAUCUUUCCAAGAAUGUCUACAUGUAUCUGUUUCUCACAGCCUGACACGAGAAGGUACACGAUGCCAAUUUGUCCCCUUAUGGGCAAUGAUAGUUUUAGCUACUUGGAUAUGGUAGAUGUUGCCACAUUUCCUUAUUGUAAACAUAACUUUCUUUUUGUAAUUAAUAUUUUGUUCCUCACAAACUUAAACCCUAUAGAUUAAGUACCUAUUAAUGAACCUUGCAUAGAUCAAAUAGCACACUGAUGAUUGCAAAAUAGAGACUCUAUCAUUACUUUCCUAUUUUUAGAUGGUCUUAGAAAAAAGUACAUACAUGUUGAGGAAAAGCUCUUUACAUACUUUGUUUCCCAAUCUUUGUAUCAUUAUGGCCCUAUGGAUUCUUUUUAUAUUCACUGUAAUAAACCAUUACUAUUCUUCUUUUGUUAUUGCUGGUUUUACUGAAGUAGCUGUACAUUCAUAUGAAGUUGUAGGAAAUAACAGAGAGCCCAACGGUAAUGUUUUGCAAAACUAUAGUAUAAUAUCCUCCUAAACAGGGUAUUGACAUUGAUGCAAUCCACUGAUCUGAUUCAGAUUUUCCUAGUUUUGCUUUUAUUCAUUUGUGUGUGUGUAUGUUCUAUACAUUUUUAUCACCUGGUCCGUUUGUGUAUAAACAACACAGCCAAGAUACUGAACAAUUCCAACUCCACAGGGAGUCCUUUUGUUGCCUUUUAGAACCACAUUCACCUUCAUGCCAUCCCACCCCAUCCCUAACCUUUGGCUUGUAUCUUCCAUUUCUCAAAUUUGUCAUUUUAAAUGUUAUGUAAAUUGACUCAGGUAGGAUGUAACUUUUGGGGAUUGGCUUUUUUCUCUCAGCCUGAUUCCCUUCUGACAGAUCCACACAUGUAUCAGUAAUUUAUUCCAUUUUAUUGCUAAACAUUCCAUGUUGUGGUUACAUCACAAUGUAUUUAACCAUUCACCUACUGAAGGACAUCUGGGGCCAUUUGGGAGCCUUUAGAAAUAAAACUGCUAUAGAUAUUCAUGUGCAGGAUUUAUGUGGACAUGUUUUCAUUUAUCCAAGAUAAAUGCUCAAGGGGCUAAUUGCUGAUUCUUAAGAGCUGGAGGCCGAGGAGUGGUGCAAGCACCUCUGCAUGGAGUGUCUGGGGACCAGGCUCAAUGAUAUCAGCCUUGGGGAGCCCGACCUUCUGGCCGCAGGAGUGCAGCGGGAACAGAAUGAGAGAUUCAACGUGUAUCUUAUGCCUACACCAAACCUGGAUAUUUAUGGUGAAUGCACAAUGCAGAUCACUCAUGAAAAUAUCUAUCUCUGGGAUAUCCACAAUGCCAAGGUCAAACUGGUGAUGUGGCCUCUCAGCUCACUGAGGAGAUACGGUCGGGACUCAACGUGGUUCACGUUUGAGUCAGGAAGAAUGUGUGACACAGGAGAAGGACUAUUCACUUUUCAAACAAGGGAAGGAGAAAUGAUCUAUCAGAAGGUUCAUUCUGCGACACUGGCCAUAGCUGAGCAACAUGAAAGAUUAAUGCUAGAAAUGGAACAGAAGGCCCGGCUUCAGACAAGCUUGACUGAACCAAUGACAUUAUCCAAAUCAAUAUCUCUUCCUCGCAGCGCGUACUGGCAUCACAUCACUCGUCAGAACAGCGUUGGUGAAAUCUACAGUUUGCAAGGUCAUGGGUUUGGUUCGUCAAAGAUGUCUCGUGCACAGACAUUUCCCAGCUACGCCCCAGAACAGAGUGAAGAGGCCCAGCAGCCGUUGUCGCGGUCCAGCAGCUAUGGAUUCAGCUACAGCUCCAGCCUCAUCCAAUGACACACAGAGAGCCGCUGUUGACUAGAGAGACAGUCUGUCCUGGACCCGUCUGUGGGGUCAUUACCCUCUGCCUCCUGGAAGACCAAUUGCAGUACAAAUUGAAAUGGGUCGGCUCUAGCCCCAGUCCCAUUGGAAGGUUAAAAACUGGAGUUCUGCUUCCUUGAUUCAGUGGCUAAGUCCUUUAUUUAUUGAAUUUCUUUGGGGGAAUCUAUGUUUUACAUAAAUAGAAUCCAAAUCGUAUGAACAGUUAUUUAAAUAAACAAAAUUCUUUGGGUCUGACAGUAACAGAAACCUCAGCACUGGGAAAAGUUGCCCACACUGGGGUAUGCCUGGGUGAUGGGCACCUCUCACUGACCUCACAGCGCAGUCCGCCCAUCUGAGCACAGGGUCUGUCCUUAGACAUAAUGGUGACCCUCCACAAGCUCUGUGGCUUUUAAAGUUCUGACAGGGAUAAAUACAGUAAGCUCUGCAAAUGACAUCGUAGCUGCAUAUAAAUAAACCCAGUGACAAUUAAAGGAACAUGAAAUUCAGAACACACUAUUAAGCAGGGCCCUGUAGCUCUACUCGUGUGUGUGUGUGCGUGUGUGUGUGUGUGUGUAGACAAAUGGAUAUUGCUAUAUCCAUCUAUAUAUAACAAGUAUAUAUCAAACAUGUGCUGAGGGUGACAGGAUAUGCUCACUUAAAUUGUUGAAAACCAUAAUUUGGUGCAUUAAAGUUAAGAUUGUUAUGUUGAAUAGCUAUUUUUAAAAUAGUGCUGUAAAAAAAAAAAAAAAAAAGGCUUCUUAUUAGCAAAAGUAUAUGUAAUCCAGUCUGUUCCUAACAAGUGUAAGCAAAAAUGUGAGAAGGGGAACAUUCAGAAGCAAAAGAACCAGUCUAGCUGUCCUACACAUCAUGUCAUACCCUGUCUUUCUGGUGAGCGUUUCCUUGUUGCUGACAAUGUUGCUCCCUGUGGCCAUCCAUCUGAGCUACGUGAGGAGGAUUCCAUGUGAACGCCGAUCAGCUUCCAUUUAACCUUGAGAGAAAAGAGAGGUUCUAAAUGAAGAACUCUUUAAGAAAGAAAGAAUACACCCAUAAAGAACUCAGCUAUUUUGCAGUAAAGAGAAGAACAAAAUGGGUACAGGAUUGUGGAUAUCAUAGAUGCUGUUCUCACACAACCACUGGGGGCUUGUAAUUUACUGUGUAACCAGAACUUGCAGGGCUUUAUUUUUUCUUUUACUGGACACAGGUUGUCUGAGAUUAUAAGAAAUAAAAUAGAUCAAUAAUUUUCAUCAUCCCUGACACUGAUUACAAACCUACAGUGUUUAAAGGGAGGUAGUGAAUUCCACGGAAACUGAGUUUGGCUAAUUCAGGUCAACAAAGAUAUAUUUGCCCUUAAUUCUGGAGUUAAGUAAAAAUAAAAAUUAUCCUGCCUGAAUCAUCUGAUGCUUUGUGCCUAAGAUGGUUAUCUCUCAAAUACUCUAGGGUGGGUUUAAAGAACAGUGAGCUCAGGUCACGCAAGAUGAAAACCCAGGUUUUUUUUUUCUUAAUAGGAAAAUUUUUUAAACUAUCCAAAUUAGUCUGUUGAAAGGGUACCUUUUUUGCUGAUCUCUGAUGAGUUGUCUUUUCAUCCCUAUCUGUAGCUUGAGUGCAGAUUGACAAUUCAUUUCAGUGAAUUACUACCGAAUAAAAGUGGUUCCGGAUCCCUCCUAGAUAAAUGUGCACUUACAGCAACUACCUAGGCUCUCCAAAUCACUCCACUCGGUAUGAAAACCCCAUCAAGAUACUAAUCGUAAGAGUUAAUGUGGCUGCAAAAAAUAAUUAUCCUAAGCUUUCAGGGAUAAAAAGAAAAUUACCCAGGUUCUCUGCACUGUGAAUUUUGCUGACACAGCGGAGGAGCAGAUGACUGGUUCCUACAACUGUACAGCCUUCCUUGAAAUCAUAGCUUUUGGGGUUAAACACUUGUGAAUUUCUUUUGCACAUGGCAUUUGCUUUUGAAAUGCCUUUAGUCAAAUACACCAGAGCAACUCCCAGCUGAGACCAUUUGAGCACAGUUCCUAGUGGGGCCACAUUCAGAGCAAGCCUCUCGCCGGCUCACUCAGUUGAGCUGUUGCUUAGACACCACAAGUUUCUACAAGGGACUUAUGGGGAACGGCCCUCAGGGGUCCUGGUUCACAUCUCAGCUUUAUUCAUGUGCUGGAAGCACAAACAGCGAGUCCAGGGAGGGAUUCUGCUAAUCAGAUGAGUCUGCUCUUGUGUCUCUUUCUUAGGAGACAAAUACCUGUAUGUAAUUGCUUCAAGAACUCCAUUUGGUUCUGAUCAUUACCAAUGAAUAUAACUGAAGGAGCACCAAAGAUCAGGCAUAACCUCGGGCCAGUUCAUUCUGAAAAUGAUGUCGUAAAAAGAGUAUGUGUGAGAGAAAUCUCCUUCCCAAGUUUUUAACCAGAUCUCGUCACAAUGAGGAGAAUGCUAUAAUCUAUCUCAUGGUACAUUUUUGGAGCUUAAUUCUAGCAUACUCCUCCAAGUACACUCACAAUUGUAGCUGAGUCAAGACUGCUAAAUGAACAGAUAGGAGAACUUAUAUUAGACUAAUAUCCUUGACACGAAGCAGGGUUCAUUGUAAUAAAAACGGCAAACAGAUAAAUCUUCUACCAAAACCAAAGAUGGAAAGUCACUGCACCAGUCUCCUGGAACUUCAUAAAAUCAAUUUCACUGGAGCAACCAGAAGGGUCAUGGAGAUGUAUACCACUCGCUUGGGCUCGUAGGUUUUUGACUGGGGAUGCCUCUACACUUUGUAAGUCAUUUCUCCCUUCAAAAAUUGUAUUAUAUCUUUAAUAUAUGUGUAUUUUUCAAUGCGAGGGAGGAAUUACUAUGAACCAAAGAUAUCUUUUGGCUCCUUCUGAAAGUGACUCAGUUUGAAUUCCAUUCAGAUUUGUACAGAUAAAUAGAUGGUCACCAUUUCUGCAUCAGGUUGGAAGAGACCAAUGAUAAAGGAACCCAACGUAAGGAAUAGCAGUUCUGAAAAUAGACAAAGCCUAGAGGAGGUAUCUAUUUCACUGAGAGAUUACACGAGGGGACUUAUUUUUUAUGUUCCCAAUUUUUUCUUCUGAUAAUAUUAAUCAAUGUACACAUGAUUGAUGCAUGAUAUUACACUUAAAAUGCAGGAGAGUACAAAACAACCUUGAUCCAAUAGUUUCCUAUUCUGGGGGGUGGGGGCAGAGGCGGAAAAGAAAACACAUCUUUCACUUACUUAUUGAACAAACAAUAAGCACUCAGAACUAAUUUAUUUAUGCAGGUUGCAAAUAUGUAUGAAGCAAUAGGUUCUGGCCACUGCCACAAUUUGAAAUCAAUAAAAUAAGAAAUAUAUAUUUAUAUAUGAGGGAAGAUGCUGUUUGAUAGAGCAUGUGAAAUCAAUGGAAACAUAUUUAUUAAAAGUAAACCUCACCUUUUUCACCAAAUAGUAACUAGAGAACUAGUCCUAGUAUCUUGCGUAAUUCUUCUCUGUCUUCAUUGGGAAAUUAUGUUUGAAAAUCUUUCAUCACCUAUAAAAUGGUGAGCCUCUUGUACUUUCUAUUCAGUGUAGAAAGAGUGGACUGAUAAAUAACUUUACAUUGUUGGUAGUAGUUUCUACAGAUCCAGUUUAUUGCAUGUCGUAUCUUUAUUGUAGAUAUUAAAAACACAUGAUAAAAAUUGAUGUGUGCCCCUCCUUGUUUGGCCAGUAUCACAGAAAACUUUGUAAAAAAGCAUGGGGACCCUACUCCCUAGAUUAUUUGAGCCAUUUACUAAAAUUGGCCAUUAGUGAUACAGUGAAAACAAGCUAAGGAAAUGAUAUUCUCCUAAAAAGUUAUAUUCCAGUUUUGAUUAUUAUAACACAGCACAAUAAAUGGGCAGUAUACGUCUAAUGGAACUGAGAUUUAAGGCUUUAACAAUUCGUGUUUUAAAAUAUUAUAUUGAAGACUGCACAAAGAGAAAAUUAUACAUGUUUCUCCAAUCCUGUGAUCAUGUCUGUAAAUACCUUGCAAUUUCAAAUUACUUCAUCCGUCAUUAACUAUAUGAUCUCCCAAACACAGCCUUCUCAAAAUCGAUAAAAAUUUGCCACUGAAUAUGCAUUAAUAGCUAUAACAAUGGGUGACAUGCCACACAAAUUUAGCUUAUGCAAUUUAUGGGGUGUGUGUUUGCAGACUAUGAAAUGUAUGAAGUGCAGUCUCCCAUGGAGAGAAUAGAGAGGCAGGAUGGCAACUAGUCAUGAACGCAACAAUUUAGGUUAAAUGAUAAAGAAUACAAUGAAAUGUCCAGAGUAACACUUGGUCUCUACCUUUCUAACAUUCUAACCCAAGGCCAGUGUCAUGGGCUUGGCUUUCUUCCCUGUCGCCUCAUACUGAGUAUGCAAUUUACAGAGGACAUCUGUUGCUUUAUGUCUUAAGGCCACUAGAGGAAGUCACUACAUUCCCAACAAAGAUGUGUCUUUCGGCUUAGUGAAAAACAUUUAACAAGAAACAAUGUGUAACCAAGUCCCCACAGUAAAAUGUGUCUUCAGAAACAUGAGAAUCACUUUUAUAUAGCCAACCUCAUUUGAAUUUUAUCAUGAACAUAAAUUAUCGGUGAGACUGGUGUGCGGGGCUGGAUCUGUGAGACAAGCUCACACUCUCAUGUGUGCAUUCUCUAUUAACAUAUUUGGAAGAUUGCCCACAUUUUCUCUGCAGACCUGCCACAAAUCCUUACCUUCUUACUGAAGAAUGUGACUAUUGUAGCAUUCGUGCAAUUAUGCCAGCAGAGGAGGCACUAGACAGUUUAUAGACUCUUAUGGAAGUUGGGCACAUUUCCCAGGCAGGUGGAAUGCUAGCUAGAUCUAGAAGCACCCUUAAAGGUCAUGUAGAAUCAAGGUCCCACUUUAUGUUUCCCUUGGGAGAAAACUGAAACCCAUGGAUGCUGUAAUUUGUUUAACGGCAAAGAAAGAGCCAAGAAUUGUUUCUCGUAGUUCCAGGGUCCUGAUCUAGGAAUGUUUCCUUGGCUCCAUGGCAUCUCCCAGUUUGACAUAGUGGGAGCUGAGAAAUGCCAUAUGGCCUCAAAAUAAAUAAACCCUUGUACAUUUAAGUGUUUUCCCAGAUUUUCAGAUGCCUCUACUCUUGCUGAACUCAUCACCAGCUGUAUCAGUAGAGAGGUGUUAUGGGGCAAUUCAUUAGAUUUCUGGUAGGUCAUGAAUGGUUGGUAUAAGCUUUAUUUACUCAUAUAUUGUCAUCCAGUUCUUUGAAAUUCAAUCUUAUCCUAAAGUGGUAGUCAAAGUAAAACACAUUAAGUAGGUGUUUGUGUUUAGCAGUCCUACUAAUUCAUCACAAUCACAUAGUAAUUGUGAUUAUAAUUUUUGGAAUCUUUAUCACUUUCUAGCACUUUACGGUGUCAUUAUUUAUGGCAUUUUUAACAACUUUGUUGCAUAAUUGAUAACAUCAGGGCUACAUUUUUUUCAUGUGAGCCUCAAGAAGCUUCCAUUAUCAACAAGAAUUGGGGAAAUGACUUUUUUACAUUAUAAUACCUUAUAUAUUAGGUUUUUCCUGAUAAUCUUCAGUAGACAAUGAUUUAAAUUAACUGAAGUUUAAAUAAGAAAUAUGUUAAAAUUACUAAAUAAUAUGAAAACCACAUUAUACUUGUAAUUUUCAGACACUUUUCUCCUACCUUAAGAUUUUAACAUCUUGUAAAUAUUAAUAUUUGAAGGGGAGAGGAAAAAUACAUUUGUAGUAGAAAUAUUCCCUCUAACAAUUCUGUUUAACUAGUAAGUUUUUUUUAAGUUAUCUUCCAUGCCUGCUUCCCUAGUCUGAACUCCACAUUCCAGUUGUCAGAAGAAUGAAUGGAUUUAAAUUUUCUAAUCAUUAUUUUGGGCCCAUGUUAGCAGUUGAAACAAUUAAGUUCCUCACUCUUUCCUGCUUUUAGGAUGAUUUUAGACUGUGAGCAUAAAAUCAACCCUUUCUGUCAGCACAGAAUUGAACAUCGAAUGGAGCAAGGUCUACACUCUCAGCCUGUAGCUGUGCUAAUGUUAGGAUUGAAUUGUUCUAUUAAUUCCCUCAAGAGACCCACAGCCUCAAAAGAGUUGCUUAUUAUCAGAUGUCCGAAAUUCAGAAACCCAAAGUCAGGCAAAGAAGGAAACUGAGAUAAUGAUUUAAUUUUUUUAAGUCACUGCAGGAUUUCUCUCAAAGAAAACAUCUGAAAAUGGUUGAGAAAGUAGUUCCAGAUCAUUAACUAUUUUACAGAGGGACUGAAAGCCAGGGAAAAUAAAGAACAGAAUGAUAGUAGUAUCUUGAUAUUAAAUUUGCAUCAGAAAUGAGCAAAAUAUGUCAAUAUGAAAUAAUUUGAAAUCAAAUUCAGAUUCACAUGUAUAGUGCAUAGUUCAAGAAAUAAUGCUUACUCUUGUAAAAAAAAAAAAUAUAUAUAUAUGUAUCAGCAGGUAGAGUGUGGGAGCUCCAACUUUGUUGUGAAAGCUGAUAACAGAGUAUGAUUCUUUCCAGUUACAAAAUACUGUAUUACUUUAGUUAUAGCAAGCAGUACAUAAAUGACAUCAACAACUCAGGCUGCUCCCUGACAUAAAAGCCAGUUCCAUCUUUACUGCAGAUGACAGGAGACUUUCCAAGACCUGCAGAGGCCCCCUCCACCCCAACCUUAGUGCAUGCUCACACACACACACACACACACACACACACACACACACACACACAUUUUUGGCUUUUGACCCACUCUGUGUGUUCCACUGAAGUUAUCUUUUCCUUAAUAGAUUCACACAGAAUUACCCCAUCCUGCAAAAUCCUUAUCCCUAUGAAUCUCUAAAAUAUAUUAAAUAAUGUGUUAUAUAUUUGCUUUUUGUAAAUCUUUAUUUAAUUAAUUUAUAUAUACUUUGUGAAGUCUUAUACUGUACAUCAUAAAGCGAUGUCAUCUGUAGUUGGUUCAAUAUAAUGUUUAUGAUCAUUUUGAUAAGAAAUAACUUUGGACAUUAGGCCCUUGUUAAGAAAUAAAACACCCAUUAUAAAUUUGCUUCUGUUGGAAAAUACAUGAUUUGGCAUACUUCAUUUUUAGUAACAAUCUAUUCUAGAUAAAUGAUAAUUUGGGGACAUCUGUACUUAAAAACUAGCUGAACUACGUUUUGGGAUGAGAUGCAAAGCAACAGCUGUCCCUGGAACUGAAAUGUGAAUUUCUAGCAGAACAGAAAAUAUUAUAAUAAUGAGGCAAUAAUAAAAUUAGGAAAUUAAAUUAUUUUUAAAUCUGUCUGUGUGAUUUUUCCCCUUGGUAAAAAUACAUGAAAUACAUAAUUGAAAAAUUACCUUCUUCUGAAGUCGUAGUUUUUAAUCUUAACCAUCAAUAAAUAAACCUAUUGUUAACAAUGUCUUAUUCAUAAUUCUAAAAAAUUUACAAAUGAUAUUGCUAUGAGGUUGUGCACUAUUAAAGUUUGCUCCAUCACUUAAAGGUAAAGCAGUUCAAAAAUACUACUUUACAUCACAACUUUGCAUGGCUGAGAUUUUGAACAACUAAAUUGAUGGUUUUACCCACAAGUUAUUUCAUAAAGCUAACACUGUAAUAUUACUUGGUUUUCUUAUACUUUUGUUAUCAUGUGAUGAAAUGUAACUAUGUAAUUAAACAAAAUUCUGACAAUCAUAUUCUGCUAAUGUUUAAAAUGUUACUUAUUCCUUCACUUAUUAGCUUGCUAUUUUGAAAAUAAAGUGAAAGAAGGCCCUUUAUUAAAUGAAA